GGCGGACGGGCGGGCGCUUCGCCGUUUGAAUGGCUGCGGGCCCGGGCCCUCACCUCACCUGAGGUCCGGCCGCCCAGGGGUGCGCUAUGCCGUCGGGAGGUGACCAGUCGCCACCGCCCCCGCCUCCCCCUCCGGCGGCGGCAGCCUCGGAUGAGGAGGAGGAGGACGACGGCGAGGCGGAAGACGCCGCGCCGCCUGCCGAGUCGCCCACCCCUCAGAUCCAGCAGCGGUUCGACGAGCUGUGCAGCCGCCUCAACAUGGACGAGGCGGCGCGGGCCGAGGCCUGGGACAGCUACCGCAGCAUGAGCGAAAGCUACACGCUGGAGGGAAAUGAUCUUCAUUGGUUAGCAUGUGCCUUAUAUGUGGCUUGCAGAAAAUCUGUUCCAACUGUAAGCAAAGGGACAGUGGAAGGAAACUAUGUAUCUUUAACUAGAAUCCUGAAAUGUUCAGAGCAGAGCUUAAUCGAAUUUUUUAAUAAGAUGAAGAAGUGGGAAGACAUGGCAAAUCUACCCCCACAUUUCAGAGAACGUACUGAGAGAUUAGAAAGAAACUUCACUGUUUCUGCUGUAAUUUUUAAGAAAUAUGAACCCAUUUUUCAGGACAUCUUUAAAUACCCUCAAGAGGAGCAACCUCGUCAGCAGCGAGGAAGGAAACAGCGGCGACAGCCCUGUACUGUGUCUGAAAUUUUCCAUUUUUGUUGGGUGCUUUUUAUAUAUGCAAAAGGUAAUUUCCCCAUGAUUAGUGAUGAUUUGGUCAAUUCUUAUCACCUGCUGCUGUGUGCUUUGGACUUAGUUUAUGGAAAUGCACUUCAGUGUUCUAAUCGUAAAGAACUUGUGAACCCUAAUUUUAAAGGCUUAUCUGAAGAUUUUCAUGCUAAAGAUUCUAAACCUUCCUCUGACCCCCCUUGUAUCAUUGAGAAACUGUGUUCCUUACAUGAUGGCCUAGUUUUGGAAGCAAAGGGGAUAAAGGAACAUUUCUGGAAACCCUAUAUUAGGAAACUUUAUGAAAAAAAGCUCCUUAAGGGAAAAGAAGAAAAUCUCACUGGGUUUCUAGAACCUGGGAACUUUGGAGAGAGUUUUAAAGCCAUCAAUAAGGCCUAUGAGGAGUAUGUUUUAUCUGUUGGGAAUUUAGAUGAGCGGAUAUUUCUUGGAGAGGAUGCUGAGGAGGAAAUUGGGACUCUCUCAAGGUGUCUGAACGCUGGUUCAGGAACAGAGACUGCUGAAAGGGUGCAGAUGAAAAACAUCUUACAGCAGCAUUUUGACAAGUCCAAAGCACUUAGAAUCUCCACACCACUAACUGGUGUUAGGUACAUUAAGGAGAAUAGCCCUUGUGUGACUCCAGUUUCUACAGCUACGCAUAGCUUGAGUCGUCUUCACACCAUGCUGACAGGCCUCAGGAAUGCACCAAGUGAGAAACUGGAACAGAUUCUCAGGACAUGUUCCAGAGAUCCAACCCAGGCUAUUGCUAACAGACUGAAAGAAAUGUUUGAAAUAUAUUCUCAGCAUUUCCAGCCAGACGAGGAUUUCAGUAAUUGUGCUAAAGAAAUUGCCAGCAAACAUUUUCGUUUUGCGGAGAUGCUUUACUAUAAAGUAUUAGAAUCUGUUAUUGAGCAGGAACAAAAAAGACUAGGAGACAUGGAUUUAUCUGGUAUUCUGGAACAAGAUGCGUUCCACAGAUCUCUCUUGGCCUGCUGCCUUGAGGUCGUCACUUUUUCUUAUAAGCCUCCUGGGAAUUUUCCAUUUAUUACUGAAAUAUUUGAUGUGCCUCUUUAUCAUUUUUAUAAGGUGAUAGAAGUAUUCAUUAGAGCAGAAGAUGGCCUUUGUAGAGAGGUGGUAAAACACCUUAAUCAGAUUGAAGAACAGAUCUUAGAUCAUUUGGCAUGGAAACCAGAGUCUCCACUCUGGGAAAAAAUUAGAGACAAUGAAAACAGAGUUCCUACAUGUGAAGAGGUCAUGCCACCUCAGAACCUGGAAAGGGCAGAUGAAAUUUGCAUUGCUGGCUCCCCUUUGACUCCCAGAAGGGUGACUGAAGUUCGUGCUGAUACUGGAGGACUUGGAAGGAGCAUAACAUCUCCAACCACAUUAUACGAUAGGUACAGCUCCCCACCAGCCAGCACUACCAGAAGGCGGCUAUUUGUUGAGAAUGAUAGCCCCUCUGAUGGAGGGACGCCUGGGCGCAUGCCCCCACAGCCCCUAGUCAAUGCUGUCCCUGUGCAGAAUGUAUCUGGGGAGACUGUUUCUGUCACACCAGUUCCUGGACAGACUUUGGUCACCAUGGCAACCGCCACUGUCACAGCCAACAAUGGGCAAACGGUAACCAUUCCUGUGCAAGGUAUUGCCAAUGAAAAUGGAGGGAUAACAUUCUUCCCUGUCCAAGUCAAUGUUGGGGGGCAGGCACAAGCUGUGACAGGCUCCAUCCAGCCCCUCAGUGCUCAGGCCCUGGCUGGAAGUCUGAGCUCUCAACAGGUGACAGGAACAACUUUGCAAGUCCCUGGUCAAGUGGCCAUUCAACAGAUUUCCCCAGGUGGCCAACAGCAGAAGCAAGGCCAGUCUGUAACCAGCAGUAGUAAUAGACCCAGGAAGACCAGCUCUUUAUCGCUUUUCUUUAGAAAGGUAUACCAUUUAGCAGCUGUCCGCCUUCGGGAUCUCUGUGCCAAACUAGAUAUUUCAGAUGAAUUGAGGAAAAAAAUCUGGACCUGCUUUGAAUUCUCCAUAAUUCAGUGUCCUGAACUUAUGAUGGACAGACAUCUGGACCAGUUAUUAAUGUGUGCCAUUUAUGUGAUGGCAAAGGUCACAAAAGAAGAUAAGUCCUUCCAGAACAUUAUGCGUUGUUAUAGGACUCAGCCGCAGGCCCGGAGCCAGGUGUAUAGAAGUGUUUUGAUAAAAGGGAAAAGAAAAAGAAGAAAUUCUGGCAGCAGUGAUAGCAGAAGCCAUCAGAAUUCUCCAACAGAACUAAACAAAGAUAGAACCAGUAGAGACUCCAGUCCAGUUAUGAGGUCAAGCAGCACCUUGCCAGUUCCACAGCCCAGCAGUGCUCCUCCCACACCUACUCGCCUCACAGGUGCCAACAGUGACAUGGAAGAAGAGGAGAGGGGAGACCUCAUUCAGUUCUACAACAACAUCUACAUCAAACAGAUUAAGACAUUUGCCAUGAAGUACUCACAGGCAAAUAUGGAUGCUCCUCCACUCUCUCCCUAUCCAUUUGUAAGAACAGGCUCCCCUCGCCGAAUACAGUUGUCUCAAAAUCAUCCUGUCUACAUUUCCCCACAUAAAAAUGAAACAAUGCUUUCUCCUCGAGAAAAGAUUUUCUAUUACUUCAGCAACAGUCCUUCAAAGAGACUGAGAGAAAUUAAUAGUAUGAUACGCACAGGAGAAACUCCUACUAAAAAGAGAGGAAUUCUUUUGGAAGAUGGAAGUGAAUCACCUGCAAAAAGAAUUUGCCCAGAAAAUCAUUCUGCCUUAUUACGCCGUCUCCAAGAUGUAGCUAAUGACCGUGGUUCCCACUGAGGUUAGUCUCUUGUAUUAAACUCUUCACAAAAUCUGUUUAGCAGCAGCCUUUAAUGCAUCUAGAUUAUGGAGCUUUUUUCCUUAAUCCAGCUGAUGAGUUACAGCCUGUUAGUAACAUGAGGGGACAUUUUGGUGAGAAAUGGGACUUAACUCCUUCCAGUGUCCUUAGAACAUUUUAAUUCAUCCCAACUGUCUUUUUUUCCCUACCAUUCAGUGAUUACUGUCAAGGCUGCUUAGAAUCCAAACUUGGAUUUUUGACUCUGGCAAAGCUUUUAGAAAUACUGCAAGAAAAUGAUGUGUACCCAAACGUGAGCAUAGGAGGCUUCUGUUGACGUACUCCAACAGAAGAACUGUGUUUCAAGUUCAAUCCUACCUGUUUUGUGGUCAGCUGUAGUCCUCAUAAAAAGCAAAACAAAAAUUAGGUAUUUUGUCCUAAAACACCUGGUAGGAGUGUGUGAUUUUUUGCAUUCCUGACAAAGGAGAGCACACCCAGGUUUGGAGGUCCUAGGUCAUUAGCCCUCGUCUCCCGUUCCCUUUGUGCACAUCUUCCCUCUCCCCAUUCGGUGUGGUGCAGUGUGAAAAGUCCUUGAUUGUUCGGGUGUGCAAUGUCUGAGUGAACCUGUAUAAGUGGAGGCACUUUAGGGCUGUAAAAUGCAUGAUUUUGUAACCCAGAUUUUGCUGUAUAUUUGUGAUAGCACUUUCUACAAUGUGAACUUUAUUAAAUACAAAACUUCCAGGCUAAACAUCCAAUAUUUUCUUUAAUGCUUUUAUAUUUUUUUAAAAUGUUAAAACCCCUAUAGCCACCUUUUGGGAAUGUUUUAAAUUCUCCAGUUUUUUGUUAUAUAGGGAUCAACCAGCUAAGAAAAGAUUUUAAUCAAGUUGAAUUGAGGGGAUUAAUAUGAAAACUUAUGACCUCUUCCUUUAGGAGGGAGUUAUCUAAAAGAAAUGUCUAUUAAGGUGAUAUAUUUAAAAAUAUUUUUGGGUGUUCCUGGCAGUUUAAAAAAAUUGGUUGGAGAAUUUAGGUUUUUAUUAGUACCAUAGUACCAUUUAUACAAAUUAGAAAAUGUUAUUUAACAGCUGAAUUAUCUAUACAUAUCUUUAUUAAUCACUAUUGUUCCAGCAGUUUUCAAGUCAAAUUAAUAAUCUUAUUAGGGAGAAAAUUCAAUUGUAAAUUGAAUCAGUAUAAACAAAGUUACUAGGUAACUUCAUAUUGCUGAGAGAAAUAUGGAACUUACAUUGUUCAAUUAGAAUAGUGUUCUGCAAAAAUAUUUAUAAAACUUCUCAAGAUACUGCUACUGUAAUUUUAUAUGAAGAUAAGUGUAUUUUUCAAUAAAGCAUUUAUAAAUUA